GUAGAGACGAGGAUUUGCUGUGUUGCCCAGGUUGGUCUCAAACUCCUGGGCUCGAGUGAUCCACCCACCUUGGCCUCCCAAAGUGCUGGAAUUACAGGCAUGAGCCACCAGGCCUGGCCUGCUUCAAAGAAAAUAAAAAAAAGACAAUGUGUUCAUAGAUAGGCACAUAUAUUGUUAUGAGGUUAAUGAAAGAAAUGAUUAAAUUGUUUCUCAUCCAAGUUUAAACUUUAAAAAGAAUUUGGAUUACUACAUAAUUCUUUAAAAAAGAACCAUAAACUGUAUACAAUUUUUUUAAAAAAGACUUUAGGUAAUUUUUAAAAUUUGGAUAAUUUCAAUAUAAUUGAUUUAUUUUCUAAAAAUCUGUAUAUUUUAUUUUACUCAUUUAAAAAUGUUGUCCUGAGAAGGUUUCAUAGGAUUCACUAGAUUCUCCGAAGUUUCAUCGCACAAAAAUGAUUCAGAAACAUUAUUCUAGUUGCUGGAAAUAAAGUAGCAAACAAGUCAGAUACGGUCCGGGCUUCCACAGAACUUACCUCGGGGGAUGAGGAAAGAGGAAGAUGACAAACAAUAAACAAAGAAUCAGCAGAUUUCUAGGUAGUCAUAGGGCUAUGUAUACAACUCAUGUGUGUGUGUGUGUGUGUGUGUGUGUGUGUGUGCCUGUAUGUGUUUCCUAUACUAUAUAUGAGAGUAGGAGCAAUAAGAGAGAAACCAUAUCAUGUACAGCAUGUAGACUAGGGUAAUAAGUUUCAGUUUUCUUCUAAUUACAUUGUGUGUUCAUCAAAGAUUUUUUUAAAUUGUGAUAAAAUACAUAUAAUGUGAAAUUUACCAUCUUAAUCAUUUUAAGGGUACAGUUCGGUGGCAUUAAGUACAUUUACAUUGUUGUGUGACUGUUGCCACCAUCCAUCCACAAAACUCUUUCAUCUUGCAGGACUAAAGCUUUAUACCCAUUAACCAAUAACCCCUUCCUUUCCCCAACAUUGGAGCAGUGACAAGACGUGUUUUACAUUUUAAAAGCAUGACUUCAUUUAAAAAACGUGAAGACAAUGUUGCUAGGCAAGAAUAGAACCACCAACAGGAAACCAGUUAGGAAAUACGGCAGAUGAGAGGUGACAGUGGAUGAACUAUGGUGUUGGCAGAAAAGGAGUUUGAAGUGGACUUUGGCAGUAAAUCAGACAGGAUUAGAUGAUGGGCUGGAACAAGUAUGGAGGAGGACUUGGGUUCUGUUUCGGACAUGGUAAGUCUGAGUUGUGUCUUUGCCAUCCAAGUGGAAGUGCCUAACAGUUGGGUAGACAAGUCAGAGUUCAGGAAAAACACCAGAAUAUAUUGUGGAGUCCUGGGCAAAUGAGUGGUAUUUGAAGCAAUGGGAACGGAUGAGAUAAUCCAGGAAGAUAAUAUAGAUAAAGAACAAGCCCGGGAAUAAUCUCUGGGGCAUUGUCAUCGUUUAGAGGUCAGGUUGAGAAGAAGAGAACUUUAUGAGUGGCUUGUCCAAUCUUACUUAGAGAACUUAGUGUUGUAGGAACUUGGAUCUUGGCUCAGACAAACAGACAAAGCUACCAGUUGAAAAUUCCAUCAGGCUGGUCUUAGCCAGGUUAUACUGGGUCUGGCCAUGAGAGAGGGGUAAUCUCAUCUUCUAAUUUAUAUUUACACCUAGGACAUCUAAGAUGGUGCUGGGAUGGGGGAGGCAAGACAGCGCCAAAGAGAAAUUGUUCUCUAUUAUUUUAUUCUUUAUAAUUUCAACUUGUAUUUUAGAUUCAGGAGGUACAUGUGCAUGUUCGUUACACUGGUAUGUUGCAUGAUGCUGUGGUCUGGGGUGUGACUGAUCCUGCCACCCAGUUAGUGAGAAUAGUACCCAAAAGGAGACCUGUUCUGAUGAUGUGUGUGGUCCUCACCACACUGCCCUGCCUCACCUUUUCCAUAGCAGUGACUGAGGUUCAAAAGAGCAUUAAUGGGUCCGCUGAUGUCUUACCUGAUAUGUUACCUGACCUGCCCGUAUCUCUGGUUCUGUUAUCCCUGAUCAUGGUUGAUAUUAUUGAAAAACUCAGGAUAUAUCCUCUUAGAGGGAGUCAAAAGAGUAGUGAAAAUGGACACAUCCAUUCAACCUCUUUGCAACACAUAAAAACUGUGACGGAGCAAGUGAGGCAAAGUCCAGAAAACGCUGCAUCUCCCCAGGCAACCAACAGCACCCAGGUGUCGCAGCCAUCAGGAGCCAUGACACGGAGCCAGGAGUCUGUGUUCAUGGGACCCCAGGAGCCCUCCUGUGACUCCGGAAUCCUGAGAAUGAUGUCCCGGCGAGAUGUCCGGGCAGAGUUAUUCUUAUGGAGCUUUCUCCUGUGGUCUGACACGAUAGAAAUGGUGCGUGUGGCUGGUCACCCCAACGUGUACAAGUCAAGCUGGCUAUACCCAGUCUACAUAUUCAGUUUUAUUUCUCUCCUUCGAAUUACAUUCACUCCCCAAAACCCUCUUCUCAAUUCCCUGAGCGUCCUGCUGCAAGAUUUACCAUUCGUUUUUGUUAGACUUGGUUUAAUCAUUGCCCUGGGGACUAUCACACCCGUACUGGGCCUGUGUAAAAAUAUCCUCGUGACUCUCUCUUACAUUUACUUCAAUUACCUAACCAGAAUCAGGAUUUUUUCUGCCUUUGAAAUGUCUCCAUUUUAAAAAGGAAAUGGGAUCUAGUAAGGCCUCUUUGUGAUACCUGUGUGCACAUUUGUAAUCCUUCUUUUUUUCUUGGGGCGUAGGUGUUUGCACUAUAAAGGAAAUGACUAGAUUGUAGAGAAUAAGCCAUUUUUACUAACUCUAGCAUAUCAGUUUUUUUUUUUACAUAUACAAAUGGUGCUAAAUUUAAGUAAAGUAAUAUUCUUAUAAGUUGGCUCUCAGGUAUUUCUAGAAAAUGUUAGCAGCUAAUUUUAGUUAGUUAUGUAUACUGAGGUCCCCAACCCCUGGACCAUGGUCCCAGUACUGGUCCGUGAUCUGUUAGCAAGCAGACCGCACAGCACGUGGUGAACCUCAAACUGAGCGUUCCCGCCUGCAUUCCGCCUCCUGUCAGAUCAGCAGCAGCAUUAGAUCCUCAUAGGAGCCCAAACCCUAUUGUGAACUGCGUAUGCAAGGGAUCUAGCUUUCGCUCUUUAAGAAAAUCUAAUACCUGAUGAUCUGAGGUGGGACAGUUUCAUCCCAGAACCCAACCCCACCCCCAACCCUGGCUGUGGAAAAAUUGUCUUCCACAAAACUAGUCCCUGGUGCCAAAAAGGUUGGGGACCACUGAUGUAUACCACGCUUUUUCUAAGAAUACUCUUCAACGGAGCCCUUUAAAAAACUAAGAACCUUUUCCAUCAAGUUAGCCCAAGAAUAAGAUUUUUAUCUUUUAUAUAGAUAGCAUUAUAUGAAUUGAUUGAUUAAAUUUAGUUUUAAAAAACACACUUGAAAUUAUUGAAUAAUUUUUAGGUUAUACUUUUUUUUUUUUUUUUGAGACGAUGUCUCGCUCUUGUCCCCUAGGCUGGAGUGCGAUGGCGCGUUCUCAGCUCACUGCAACCUGUAUCUCCCGGGUUCAAGCGAUUCUCCUGCCUCAGCCUCCCAAGUAGCUGGGAAUACAGGCACCUGCCACCACGCUGGCUAAUUUUUGUAUUUUUAGUAGAGACGAGGUUUCACCAUGUUGGCCAGGCUGGUCUCAAACUCCUGACCUCAGGUGAUCUGCCCACCUCGGCCUUCCAAAGUGCUGGGAUUACAGGUGUGAGCCACCACGCCCGGCUGGAUUAUACUUUUUAAAAAUUUGAAAAUUGUAGUUUUAGGGGUUCCUUCAAAGGUGGAAUUAUAUUCUUUAUUCCAUUGUGGCAAGGGACUUUUAUUCAAUAAAUUGAUUUCAGCAUAAAAAGCAAUUCACUUUAACAGAUAUUUGGCUCAGUUUAAGGCUUAGCUGUAUUGCCAGUACUGAAGUACUAAUAUGAGUGUUGUUUAGUAUAAUGAAGUCAAGGUACAUCAGUAAUACCAAGAUAAAGUUUCAUAAUAAAAAGCCAUAAAGUGAAGACAGAGAUUUCAAAGUAAAAGAAUAUUUUAUUUGUGGAAUUUGAUACUUUGAUAAAUAAUCAAAGUACAAGCCCUGUUUAAAAUUAAAAGUUCGGCUUACAAAUAUAAUAGCCAAUGUAUCAGUGUCUUAUGUGAUACUAUAUCAUGGAUAUAUUGAUGUUAUAAAAUAAUUAGAUACAGAGUCAUGCAACUUGCUUUCACCCUGUUGGGACACUCUGAACAGUCAGCACUGUUCAUUUGAUAGUAAUUUUCAGAUGCUAGAGAGAUUUGUGAGAGGCUGAUAAUGCAAGAGUAAUGAUUUAUGUAGCCAGUUUCUUCAAUGAUCUGUGAUAACAAAUCAUUAAGAAUGAGACAUAUGGCUUAAGAAUGAAGCUUAAGAAUUUGACAUAUGGCCGGCUGUGGUGGCUCACACGUGUAAUCCCAGCACUUUGGGAGGUUGAGGCAGGUAGAUCACUGGAGUCCAGGAGUCUGAGACCAGCCUGGGCAACAUGGAGAGAUUCUACCUCUACAAAAAAUACAAAAAUUAGCUGGGCAUGGUGAUCUGCAACUAUAGUCCCAGCUACUUAGGAGGCUGGGGCAGGAAGAUUGCUUGAGCCCAGGAGGUCAAGGCUACAGUGAGCUAUGAUCAUGCCACUGCACUCCAGACUGGGCAACAGAGUGACACCCAUCUAAAAAAAAUAAAAGAGAAUUUGACGUUGUGUUAUUCUACGCUCCACCAAAUACCUCUCCCCUUGCCACCCUGUCUCCCUUUCCCUCUGUUUUAGGAUUUUUCUCACACUGUAAAAGAAGAUUUACUCACAGUUGUUAAAAGCUUGCCUUCCAGCUUUCUAAUUUGAGGUAGGUUCUAUAACCUCUGUGGGUCCCCGUUUCCACAUGUAAAAGAUGAACAUAAUACUAGUACUACAUUAAUAGGGUUAGGAGGGUUAAAGGGUAAAGAGUCCUUUGAGCACAUUUUCUGGCAAACCAUAAUAACUUGAUAAAUGCUAAGCAUUGGAACGGGUACCAAGUCUCCAAGAAACAAGUAUCUCAAUGCAGUUUUAGAAAUUUCCUGUUUUAUUCUUUUCUGUGGCCCUGCUCACCCUCUGGGAAUAAUCAUUUCAACUUUGCAUUUGUGAAAAAUAAUACAUACAAUCUUAAGGUUACUUCAGACUAUACUUUUUCAUCGAGGAGUAUUGUAUUCAAAAGUGAUCGAUCUGCUGAAUAUAUAAAUUAAAAUGGACACAAGCCUUCAUUCAUCAGACAUUUGAGUGUCUGUCCUCUGAGUUCCCAUAGAAUCUGAAUUACACCACUUUAUUCACACUUACAUUAUGUGUUUACUUUUCUGAGUGUCCUAUUAAUCUUUAUUCCUUAAAGGAAAGCCUGAGGGCAUCUUGUUUAACAAUGCAUCUCUCUCUUCAUCAAUCAACGCUGCAGGUGCUUACAAGACUUAUAACUUAAAAAAAUUAUAAUACAAGGCUCAGCGCAGUGCCUCAAGUGCCAACAGUUUCGGAGGCCUUGGCAGGCGGAUCACUUGAGGCCAAGAGUUCGAGACUAGCCUGGCCAACAUGGUGAAACACCGUCUGUACUAAAAAUACAAAAAUUAGCUGGGUGUGGUGGCACGCGCCUGUAGUCUCAGCUACUUGGGAGGCUGAGGCAGGAGAAUCACUUGAACCUGGGAGGCAGAGGUUGCAAUGAGCUGAGAUUGCGCCAUUGCACACCAGCCUGGGUGACAAGAGUCUCAAAAAAAAAAUUAUAAUACAAGUAAUUACUUUCGAAUUCUGCCAUGGGUAUCUUUUUAUUAUUAAGAAAAGCCUGUCAUCAAGGGAUUCAUUUAUGAUAUUCCUAAAUAUGAAAAUAUUUUGUGUAAGUAUAUAUUUAUCUCCAUAUUAGAACUUAGCAACAGUGCUCAGAUAAACUCAAAAGUAUUACUUGAGUUUAGAAUGCAUUUUGUAUCUAAUAUUUUAAUAUGAAUGUGCCUGAUAUUUUCGGAAGUCACAACACUAUACAAAUAAUGAAGGCAUGUACAGAAGAUUAUGUGUAGGAGGAAAAUUGAGUAGCUAAUUUAAUUUCAUUUAAUAUUUUACUUAGAGUGUAUACAUGUUUAUAGACUGCAAGUCUAUGGGAUUUAAUAGAUAUUACAGCAAAUUACACUGCGAAAACAUUGAUAGUUCUACACUGUAAUUAAAUGUUAUAUAUAUUAUUAAAAUUAUUAGGUUGGUGCAAAAGUAAUUGAGGUUUUUGCCAUUGAAAGUGGUGGUGCAUGCCUGUAAUCCCAGCUACUCGGGAGGCUGAAUCAGAAUUGCUUGAACCCGGAGGGCAGAGGUUGCAGUGAGCUGAGAUCUCGCCACUAUGCUCCAGCCUGGGCAACAGAUUGAGACUCUGUCUCAAAAAAAAAAAAAAGUCAAGUACAGUUAGUUAAAGGAAUGUGCAUUUAAAAAUUAAUCUAUGAUUAGGCUAUUAAUAUAUAGUCUAAUAAUUUUAUUGCAUUAUAAUUAUAAAGUAGUUUUAUAAUUUUAUAAAAUUUUAUUGAUGCUGUAAUUUUUAUAAAAUUUUAUUUAUUUUAUAAUUUUACAAAAAAUUCUAAUACCUGUAAUACACUUUUUAGUGCCUUUUCUUUCUAAAAGUUAAUGUUUGAAAUUACAAUGUGUAAAUGUUAUCUCGUCUUGUUUUUCUUAUUAGGGCCCCAUUUCACUGAAUGACAAUUGCAAUGAGGCAUAGGAAAGAAAAGGGAAAUGAAAUUGCUUGCUGAAGUCCUACUAUGUUCUGGGCACUAUGCUGUUUGCCUAAUACAUAAUUGCCUUGUGCUGUGUACCUUGGAGCAGGGCCUUACAUAGUGAAUAUAUCAAUAGUUGUUCACAAAAAGAGCAAUAUACCACUUAGAAGCUACAAAACUUAAAAAUGGCUACUUAUACUCCAUAGAAGAUAUAGUAAAUAAUAGAAGAAAAAAAUGAAAUGGCUAAAGACAUUUUGUUUUACAAUGGGGCUGUUUUUACAUGUUAAUUAAAAUUCUAUGUUUAAACAAA